UCCUUAGAUUCUAGAAUUACCAGUGUGACAGCUAAUGCAAUAAUGAUUUGUUUCAAAUGCCAGUGUUUAAGCUGUAUAAAGCUGAUUUUAUACAUUUUUCCAGUAGGCCGCAUUGUAGUUAAUGAAAUUAAACACACCAAUCGCAUUUGUCCCCAGGGGACGAGGAACUGAACACACCACUGGUUUAUUUUUUUAUUAAAAUAAAUUGCAGCCGGCAAGAUGGACUAAUUGCAUACAGAAUUGAAAAAGAAACAUUCCAUUGAUAUAAUUAAGCCAAUUUUCAUGGACAGAAAUAGUUAUAGUGGAUAUAAAAUAAGCAAAACCUUCACCAGAAUCUGACUUCCCUCCUUUUCUGCCCAAAAUGUUAACUAUUAAACAAAUAUGAUCUUGGAGCGGCCAGCACUCCUAUCUUCAGGCCUCGGGGCAUUGUUCCCGCGUCUCAGGCUAGGCCGGCCAGGCGGGCCAGCCCAGGCACCUCCAGACCGUGGAGGAUUUGAUGGCAAAAGCCCAAGAGUGAAGUGGUCAGACCAGGGAGAGGCCACUCCUCCCCUGCUCUGGGCCCACCAAAGCUUGGGAGCACUCCUGGCCCAGGAUGACCACCGUGGCCCUGGCUGCAGCCUAGGAGACACCCAGACUUCAGGAGCCGUGGCCCACGCCAGGCUGGACCAGGGAUGUCAGCAGCCGGCCCCUUCCACCCUGCAGCUCAGACCAACAGGGCAGCAGCAGCUCCACCUCCCCCUGACUGCUGGGCGGUGGGUGGAGGCGGUGGGUGGUGGUUAUUCCCCUCCAGAUCUGAGGGGUGGCAAAGGGCAGGUCCUACACCUCCCGGGCCAACCUGAGCCUCCUGCAUUUGCUCCGGAUGAAGGCAGUGAGCGAGGGAGUGUGGAGGGUGCAGGCCAGGCCACCCGACCAAGGUUUCUGCUCCUCUGUGCCUGCCCUUGGGGACAGAACACCCACAGAAGGGGCAGGAGCUGUGGGGGACGGAGCCCAGCGGGAGUCCAGCCUGCAGGUGUGAGGUCACUUACACGCUGGACGCACGUGAUGUCCUGCCUGCUUUUUAAGAACAGACCUGCUACAAGUUGAGCAUUGGCCUUGAGAAAAUGCUUAAACCCUGACACGCACACACACACGCGCACACACACACACACACAGAAAAAACCCUAUGGAAUUAACGGCAGCCUGUGGUGCUCUGUGGGGGAGGGGAAUGCUACAUAAGAAGCCCUGGAGGUCUUCAUUCCACUGAAUUUCACUGGAGCCUCAAUCUGCUGUGUGCCCUCCCAAGAGUUCCUCCACCUCUCUGCGUCUGGGGUUUCUCACUCUCAAAAGUGGUGCCUGCUCGCCUGCACUCUGUCUUCCCAGGGUCAGUGAAGGGAGGAGGUGUCCUGUCCCCCAAGUGCACUAGGGAGCCCGGCCCGUCUCCCGAGGUUGCCGGCAGGGGCCGGGGCUGCGGAUCAGACUGGGCAGGCGGGUCUACCCUGGAAAGCCAGACCCCCACCCUCUGCCUCCGUUUCUCUGCACCGUCUUCCCUCCCCCUACAGCCCCUACUUAAACCCAGGCGGCGCGCGCUCCCGCGUCUCUCGGGGCGCGGGUCGGGAUGUCGCAGGGAACCCAGGCAAGCGGGGGGCCUGGCGCCCACGGUGUCCCGCACGAGGUCGAGGGUCGGCGGUUGGGGACGCGGAGGCCGCCCUCCUCCGCAAGGGAGGCCAGGAGGAGGGGACCCCGGGGUCCAAGCUGGGGCUCUAGAAGGGGAGAGCGCCGCUCCCGCUGGGCCAGGGUCGGGGCGCCAGGCUGCGCGGUGUGGACGCGGGCGCUGCUCCGCGGUAGUUGGCCGCGACUUUGUGCGCGGGGAGUGGGAAGUCGGCCGAGACUACCGGCCGGCCCGGGGUCCCCCAGGCCCCGCUCCCCGACCCGGCCCACGCCGUCUGCAGCCCUCGGUGGCUCGAUUCUGAGCCCGCGGCCGCCGCUGCACCGCGGCGAGGCCCCAGCCAGCUGGCUUCGCUCGCGAAGUUUCCUUCCCGCACGGGGAAGUCGCCGGAGCUGCUCCUGGUCCUCCCGCGCCGGCGACGGGAGCUGCAGCUUCCAAGACUCGUUACACGGGUUUGAUUCAAAACCUGAUAAAUUGUAUUUAACGCUAUUUGAAAAUUUUAAACGAAAUUAUUCAAAAGAUUUUUAAUCCCGGAUAAUUUUUGUUGAAACUCUAAUUAUACAUCACCUUAAUUACCAGCCCAAGCCCCCCAAGGAUCCCUAAUUGCCUCCUAAUUGAAUAAAACAGGGGGCUAAUCGGGCCCACAGCGGCCCAGCGAGCUGCCACCAGCCUCACCUCCCCUGAGGGGCCCGGUGGGGGGAGCCCCUGGCUGCUGGGUCCCCUUCACCCAGCCUCCCGGCAGAAAUGGCAGACCUGGUCCCCUGCCCUGCGCACUGCCUACAGGAGGACUUGGGAGCCGAGGAAGCCUCGGGGCCAGGAGGGGCCAGGAUGUCGGGCUGGCACCUGCUCUGGAAGAGCCGCUCACAGGACAAGGAGGACCCCCCGAGUGGGCGUCUGGUGGUUGGCGAGCCAGGCAUGGCCGGUGCCUGUCCCCAAGGAGCCCACCCAGCAGUUGCUCCACAAGCCAGCUUGGCAAGCCCCUCCUGCCAGCUUCCGAGCCAUGGCACACCUGCGCAGCCAGGGGCUGAGGGAGGGGGCCUGUGGGUGACACACAGUCCACUGCCGUGGGGCACCAAGCCCUGGCGGCCAGCCCCGCACUCCACCCCUCCACCGCAGCCUCUGUGUUUUCGUCCGAAGCGGGGCAAGACGCUGGAUUCCCGCCGGACGUCCUGGCGCUGCUGCCCUAACCGGCCUUCAGAGGGAAGGCUGCCGUCCUGGCUCUGGGGAGGGGACUGGUGGACGGGGCCAACUGCCCCAGGGAGGGUGGGAGAAGGGAGGGCCCAGCCAGCCUGGCCUGUUUCUACGAAGAAGGAAGGAGGCUGUGAACUGGGCCGCCAGCCCCGCUUACCUCUACCCUGUCUCCAGCACACCUUCCACACGCAUCACCCUCAAACACGAGCAAGACACACACAGUCCCCAUCUAGUGGGGGCUGCAGCUCCCCCACCCCAGGGGCUAGAUGGGACUUGUGGAGAGGACACUCCCCCAGCCCUGGGGUAUGUGGCAUCUAGGACAUGGGGUCUGCCACCUAGGUGGGGAUCAGGCCUCAAGGAGCAGCUCUGAUGGGGGUGCCGACUGGCACAUCCUCCUCCUGCACAGAGGCCCCCAGCUGUGCUAUGAGGGCGAUGGUGAUCCAGAGAGCACCUUGGUGGUGCUAACCCCCCACCUGCCCACCUGGCUCACAACAGCCCUGGAAACAAUAAGCUUUUGUUAAGCAUUGAGUUUGUAAAUGUGGGGCUGCAGCAGCCCCUACCCCACCGGCCCUACCGCCCUGGCUUCAGUAGGGGGGACCCUGUCCCUGAACUGUCCUCACUCUGUUCCUGGCCCCCAGGCUCAGGUGGAGGAGGCUGUAGGUUUCCCAUCAGCUGAGCCACAGCCCCGGCUUGGGUGCCCCAGUGGCCACCUCUGUCCUUGGAAAGCUCAGCUGGAAGCCCGGGUCACCCCCGGAGCCGCCACCAUUUGGCCCUUCACAAGACCCAAUCCAGAGGACUAACCCACCUGAACUGAGGCUUGGAGUGGGGUCUCCAGGGAAACACAAACGAAAUUACACCUCCAGAUGCACACUCGGCGGUGGCCCCCGAAAUGCUGGGUCAUGGGGUCACCUCCACUGGCCUGGUUGCUGUUCUGUGCCCAGCCUGAAUACCAACCUGGUAACCAUGACCUUGCCCCUGCCCAACCCCACAGUCCCCUGACCUGGUCAGCAUUGUGGGGAGGGGAGGACCUGCUGGCUGGAGUGCUGGCCCUACCGCCUCUGACUCGGGUAAUGGACUAUGGUCCCCGGGGAAGUUCACAUCUGCUUAAAAUAUCGCCUGAUGAAAUGAAAUUCUUCAGCGGAUCCUGCCUUCUUGCUCAGGGCAGGCAGUGUGAUCCUGAACCUGCCUCAGCCACCUUGGGGGGCCUGGGACAAGCGGUCCCAGCUGUGGAGCCUGGAAGGAGGGGUUCCCAGCGCUCGGCCAAGUGUGGACAGAGGGCCGAGGCCUGGCAGUCACCUCUCAUGGGGUUUUUCCUCACUAAAGACUCUCGGGAAAAGGAAGCCAGCGCUCGGCGCUCCCGCUGGGCCCGGCUCUCCGGCCUCCUGGCCAGAUGGCUGCCAGGCACCACUUCUGGUCCUGAGCGGACCCGGUCCCGGGCCACCUUCCCCACCUGGCAGAGGUGGAGCCGGCGGAGAGCUGGGGCCUCUCGGAAGUUUCCAGGGCCGCGCGGGUGCGCCGAGUCCGCCUCUCGCUUGCAGCGAAGGCCCCGGCGUCAGCGCGGCCGGUUUCCCCUUUCUCGUUCCAGCUUAGGGCCCAUCCUGGGCGAGGGCCUGACCUGGCGGCCCACACGCAGCCCGGUGGUCCCGACUCUGAGCAGGCCCGCGGUGCACACACAGAACCGAACCCGAACACGCACACGCACACCCCACGCGCGGAGGGCCCGCAACGCCGCGCACAGACAGCCCCUUCGCGUCGGCGGCGAAACGCCCGGUCUUGUUCGCACCAAGAGGGGUCAGAGGUCACGGGAGGCCGAGGCCGAGGGCACCCGGCAGCGGAGCGCGGCGGGAAGGGGGCGCCUCACCCAGGGGCCGGGAACGGCCGAUGGCGGGGCGCAGGAGCGUCCGGCACAAACUCGGGAGCUGCUUUUCCCUGGUGCACAGAGCGCGGGGCCUACGGCCGCGGGGCAGCUGUUGGGACGAGCCGGGCGGGCCCCGAGCCGAGGGAGCGGAGCUUCGGAAAACCGCCGCGAGUCCCGCGCGCACCCGGCUCACGUUUGGGGGCUCGGCCCCGGGAGCUGCGAGGCCGGCCUGGAGGGACCCGGCCCCGGAGGCGCGGACGGAACGGCGUGGGUCGGGCGGGGACCUCGAGGGGAGCGGCCCGGGCGCCUCUUCUGCGGGUGGGCGGGCGGGCGGCCUGCAGAGGAGGGGGCGGCGGGAGCAGGCGGCGCCGAUUCCGCUCCGCGCGGCGCUGGCCGCUUCGCUGCAGCCGGGGCUUCGGCGGGGCUGCGGGAGCCGCGCUGGCCGGGCCGCGGCUCCGCCUGUCCUCACCUGCCCGCCCGCCUCACCGCGGAUGGCGCCGGCGACCGGGGCUGCGGGGUGCGCGCGGGCUGCUCGGAGGCGCUGUGGCGGGCGAGGGCGCGGGUGGCUGGAGCACCCGGCCCGCGGCAAGGACCGGCUGGCGGCAGGCGGGGCGCGCGGAGCCCGGGGCUCGGCCGAGACGGAGCGAAAGAGAAACGCAGCUCGGAACUGGCCCUUUAAGAAAACAUUCCGUGUUCGGCGCUCCCGCCCGGGGCCCGCACCCCGGACACUUUAAAAGGACCCAGGUGGCCCCGGAGGCGAGGUGACUAUCCCCCCACCCUGCCCCUGCGUCGCGGCGCGUCGCGCUGCUGCUCCCGCCCCAGCCGGGGCCGAAGAUGGGGCGGCGGCUGCGGUUUUCCACACGACUUCCUUGGAUCUCGGGGCACACGCGCCGAUAGUUCGGACGCGAGUCCGGGCUGGUUUUGCUCCGUUUUACUGCGUUUGAUUACUAAUUUAAAAGCUUUGCGUUCCCCGUCGCCCCGGCCCGCUUUUCUCCUGCAUUCUCCCCUCGGCCCCCGUCCCCGCCCUGCGAUCGCUGGAGGGGGCGUCGGGGCUCGCGCGCCAGAACCCGGCUCCUCCGAAGCCCCCUCCGGGCCCCACCGCCCCCCUCGCGCCUCCCGGCCCCCGCCUCCUCCCCUUCGCCCCCACCCAACGGCUGCUGCUUCGGGCUUCGCGGCUCAAAAACAACAGCGGAGGCGCCGCCAGCUCCGCGCUCCGCCACUGCCCAGGCCGGCGGGCGGCACUCGGACCCGCCGCCCUCGGUCCCUCGCGAGGCCACGGAGGCCAACACGCCUCGCACGGGGGGACAGCGCGGGGGCAGCCGUCCAAACACCAGGCGUCCUCGGCUGGUCGUCCCAGGGCGCCCGCACCUCUCCGCCCGCGCUCUCCUGCCGCCGCGCCCCCAAGCCCCCAAACUCCGAGGCGCUGCGGCGGAGGGGCCGGGCUGAGCGCAGGCAGGGUGGCCCGGGCCCAGGAGCCUGACGGCCUGAGUGCGGAUUUCUCAUCUGAGUAUCUGGGAAUCGAGAAUGAAUUGGAAGGAAACCGAGGCGCUGCCCUGGCCAGGUUGCUGCCCCGCACCCUUCCGGAGCACCGAAGUCCUGCCCGGCAACGGGACUUGGAGCUGCCGCAGAGUCAGCCUGAGCCCGAGGCAGGGGUCGCGCCCGCGAUGCGGGGUCUCUGCGCCGCCCCGCGAGGCUCCUGGCCUUGCCCUCCCUGCCCUUUGUUGUGUAAUAAGACCUGUGGCGGCUCCACUGAGACCCACACGUGCAACUCCGCGCCUCCGCGUUAAAGGAGGUGAAACGCAGCAGCCCUGAGAAACCCCGAGACCCCGGUGUCCUAGCAGAGGCGCCCCGGAUGGGGAGGGGCGCGGGGCCGGCGCCACCCCAGAGGAAAAGCCCAGCGGAGCCGGGUUGGGCAGGAGCUGGCGGCGGCGGUGCGCUGGGCCUUCUGCCUUGGAUCCUCCGCGGUCGGCACCGCUUCCCUGCUCAGAUUCGAACCCAGAUUCGGCUCCCAAGGCUCCCACGGCUCCAGGGUGCCCAGUCUUGCAGCCAGCUCGCCGCCCGAGCCCCGGAUGGAGGAAGCGCUCACUGGCCGCUACCUCUGCUGUUUCUGGCACCAGGUGAGUGUCGCCUAGAGAAGGGCCAUGAGCAAUGGCACAGCCCCAUUCCCUGCCGUCCUUUCGAGGGUCUAUCGACCCCUUUACCCACCCUCCCCACACCCUGACCAUCUUUCUACAGGGGUUGGGGCAGAGAACAGCUCAGUUUACAGGCCCGGCUCUGGAGGUCUUGAUCUGCCUAGCCAACUAGGGCACCGCUGCAGCUUUGCACCGCCAAGGCCGGUUCUGAACCUGCUCGCCCCAGUGGGUGGGAGGUGCUGGAGCCCAGGAACACGGGCGCUGUCUUGCCUAAACCCCGCCAAGGGCAGGUUCCCAACGGUGGGCCCAACCUGGCUGGAGCUGCUGGCUAGAAAGGACUCAAGGUCACUCCCAUAUCUCUGCACCCAGGUCCCCCUUGCUCCUGCCUGAAGCCUCUGCAGGUUUGGGAGGAGGCCUGGGGAAGUUACUAUGGUGCCUGCGAACCACUCCCACCUGCAGAGAGGGUCCCUUCCCCACCCUCACCCUGCAGCCCAGCAGAGGCCUCCUUUGCCCCUGGCCUGGAGGUAGCCAACAGAUGCCAAGGUUGUGCAGUCCUGGCCUUCUUCUACGGGUGCCCCAACUCUCUCAGGCCCUCUCCCUGCCUCCUCCUCCAGCUCAGGAGGUGGUUCUCAGAACCCUGGCCAGGCUAGGACAGGACAGCCAUCCCUGGCCUGUUGCCAGCCCCUAGGGAAGAAGGGCAGGAGGUAUGGGAGCAAGCUGGUCUGUGCCAUCUGGUCCUUGCCCUCCACCAGGCUGUUGGGUAGGGAUGGGGUCAUGGAUCUGCCUGGGAAGGGGUAGCUGCCGGUCAAGCCUCGCCAGGGAGACAGCCGGGCUGCCUACCUGCAAGGCACUGACGCAGCCCUGGCUCCAGUGGGGCAGUGUCUCCCGAGCCUGCUCGAGGAGCCCAGGCAGGCUGUCCCCAAGGCCAUGGCCCUGGCCGAGGUUGCAUCCUGGCCUGGCCAGGCCCUGCCCCCGCGUGGCCAGACUUAGAAGCGGAGAGCAGGUCAGGCAUUGAGGAGUCCCGUGGGGAAAAAGGGUGAAGCAGGGAAGAUCAGAUGCAAGUCCUCCCUGGGGCCCAGUUCUGUGUCCCUGCCUGGCAAGGGCUUUGGGGGGCUUGGAGAACAGGUAGGGCAAAUGUAGGCCCAGUGGGGAAAAGGUUGAUACUAAAAGGUCUAAGGGCAAUUUUCAAACCAAGUCUAGCUCUGCAGAGCCUUGAGGCUGAUGCCAGGCCCUGGGGCCCCUGCGCUGGGAUUGUAAGUGCUGUAAGCUCAUUCCUACUGACCUCCUUGGGUCGUCCAAGGACAGUGAGUGUGGGUUGGCCACAUAGAGGCUCCUACACUGGACAACUGCACGCUGCUGUCGAGUUCCAAAACCAAUUUCAUAGCUGGGGUCUUGGAGGCUAGAGCGGGGCUUUAACCACCAACUUCUGCUGGGGUCUGGGCAGAGAGGGAGUCCAUGGAAACUCGAUUUCUCCAUGAGCCCUGCAGACUCCCAGUGUUUCUAACGGCUGGAGACCCAUGACCAGGUUAAUUCCUUAGGGAAAAGGCCGGGUUUGAGAGCCAGAAAUGCUGGUCCUGCCGUGCUGGAGGAAGCAUCUUAUUAGCGAGUAGGAGGCCCCCAAGCCCCAGGGGUUCCCCAGAAGCCCAUUGAGUAGCAGAACUACCAUGCCGGCCUGCCCUCCACUCCCGGAAUCUACAAAUGCAUUCAAGGGCUAGAGGGCCCCUUCGCUUGGCCAGGCCUUGUGCCCCAUGCCAACUGGCAGGGUCAGAGCAGCCCCAGCUGCCCCUACCCCCAGCCCCUCAGGCCCCAGGGAGCCCUGCUUCGGGCCGUGUGUGCAGGACAGGAGGUAGGCAUGGCACCUGGCAAGAUGGACUCACCUCACCAGGUUCUUUCUCUCCCACUUUCUCUCCCCUCACCUCACCCCUUUCUCUCCCACUCCUCUGUGCUUUUUGAACUUAGCCAUGGGUUUUCAGAUACUUGGCCUCAGGCUCUAUUGAAUUCCAGGUCAAGGUUUUACUGACUCCACACCCCCACCUUGUUCCUCCGGGUAGCAAAGAAGCACACAGCCUCUGGUUUACCAACGGGCUUUCCUGGGAGAUUGGAAAUGCCCCAGGUGGGAUCCAGAUCGCCAGCGCUCACCCCACCCCCAAUACGUGGGCCACUGAGUCAGGCCAGGAUGAGGCUCUUGCUCCCCGGGCAUGUUCUCCUGCCCCAGACUUGAGCAGCAGGAGCCAGGAGACCACAGGGGCCCUUGGGGAUGGCUGACUUGGCUCCCACUAGACAGAGGGGAACAUGGAGGAGGGCUGCUUGGACCCUAUACCUCGCAGGGGACUCGAUGGGGGCUGAAUGCUGGAAGGAGCCUGCGUUUGGUCUAGAAUGGUGGGGGUGGGUGGGAGACACAAGUCAUGGAAAAGGCCAUUUCUUCCCUAUUGAGACCUCUGAAAUGACCCGAAGUGGGUGCUUCCUCCAGCAUCAUGCCUCAGCCGCACACUGGGGCUACAGGAAUCCCCCCAGACCCUGGGGUCAAUAUUUCGGGGCCCCUUUGAACCUUCUUCUCACCCGAGGCCUGGGAAACCUUCUUGUGCCCCAGAAUACUUGGAGAGGACAGGACACAGGUCCCAGUUGUGGCCCAGUGGUGGCAAGGUUCCAUUCCCUGCACUGCUCAAAGGUGGGGGCCUCCCAAAGCCGAUACCCGAUUCCUGGUCCCAGAGUGGGUAGCUGGGAGGAGUGGACUUCCUAGGAAUGUGAGCCAUGUCGCUGAUUUCGAACAAACCCCAGAUGUGUGGAAACUGACUUAUUUUGAUUGCAAGAGGGUCCUUGUCCCUUGCAGAUGGGCAGCUUCCGGGGACCGGCUUGCACGAUGCCGUGGCCACCCCAGUGGAGACCCUCUGCCCGGCUUUGUGUCCUGGCGUCCCCACCAGGGUGCCCAGCUCUCCUGCGCAGAUGUCGGGAGUAUCUGGAUGCCCCAUGGGCACUUCGAGGGCCCAAUCCGGAGUUUUUUGUUUUGUUUUGUUUUAAGAGAUUGAGACUGUGAACCUGAACUCCCUUGAUCUCCUCCCGUUGGGCCCAGGAGGGAGCCGAAUCCAGGCCCAACCGGGCUCACUGAGAAGGUGCAGGAAGCCCCCAACGACUCCUACUCGUGUGCGGCCCAUACUGGGCCAGGACGCUGCAGUGGCCGAGCCGCUGGGUGUCUGCAACGGGGAGCUCCCCCGCCGCUGGGGGCAAUAAACGGAAUCGGUUUCACACGCUUUCCCUCUUGAUCUAAGAACCUUUAAAAAUCCGCCAACGAAUGCUGUUGCCUGGAUGCGCUGCCUAUGACCUUCAGCCGUGUGUUCACGCGCGCCCGCAGCCGUGGAGUGGCGGUCCCUCCUGCCGCCCGCAACCCCGGGGCCGCCGGUCUGCGCACACCGGGAGCAACUUCGUUACCCACAGCGCCCGCGUCCUGCGGCUCGCGCGGAACUGCGCGCGGGAAGGUGGCAGAGCGACGCUCCAGAACGCUGCUUGCGUAGACGCUGCCGCUGCCUUCAGAUCCCAAUUCGGCCGCGCGCGGGCGGGGCCCUGGCAGCAACGAAAAUGGCGAGCCUCGUAGCCUUCCGGGCCCGGCGGCCACAUUCCGGGAGUCGCCAGGUGGGAGCCCGCCUUCCGUGUCCCCAAACGCCCAGAGCCCGGGACACGGGCCGGCGGCCGGGUCACCAAGCCAGUUCCCGGAAUCGGCUCGCGCCGGAAUCCAGACUCGGCUUGCAAAGCCCGCUCCUGCCGUCUCUCCGCAGCGCGCCCUGCCCCCCACUGCCGGCCCUCUUAGCUUCAAAACCAAAUUUUGCCUUUCAUCCUGAGAGAUUAAUACCCCGCAGGUGAAACCGUGGAGACGGAGCUGCGGUGGGUUUCUUUUCCACGCCUCAGUUUCCUCGUCUGUGAAAUGGGACCAGGCGCGCCUGUGCUUCUCCGGGAGUUUAUUGCAGGGCUGGCUGGAGAGAAUGGCUGGGUGGAAGCUGCCAGGAGGAGGCCCAAGGCCGCCCACCCCGUGGGCCUCGUUUGCUGAGCGGGGGUCAGAGGCGUGCGGGACAGGGCGCGCCCCACGGCGGCUCUGGAGGCGGCCCGGCCCGUCCCUGUCUCCUCCCCUCGCUCCCCCUCCCCCGGCCUUCCCGGAACUCUCCUCGCCCGCUGGGUGGAGGAGGGGCGAGGGCCGACUCCGCCGCCCCUGGGGUCUCCCUCCUCCCACCCCCACCGCAGAGUCUGGCCCGCCCUGGGCUUUCCUCUCAGGUCCCUUUGGGUCUCCAGAAGCCCGGAGGUUUCGCGCAGACUCGAACCUGAGAUGACACCACCCAGCACCCCAAAUCCUGCAGAGUGUGGAGGGGAUCUGGGGAGAAGGCAGGGGCUGCCCGGGCGCUCUGGCUGCUGGGGGUGGGGGACAGGGCCUGCCGGGGAAGCGGGUCGGGGGAGGACUGGAGACCCAGGCUCCCCUAGGUACAACGAACCUCGCGGGAGGGAAUACGCCAUCCCCGUACCCACUUCCGAGGACGUAGGUCUUUUGGCACCGGCGGCAGCCGCGUUCCCACACAUCUGGGCGGGGCCCCGCAGCAUGGCCUGGGGAGCUGAGGCUUCGGGAUCCGGCACAAACUACCAUUCUAGGUGUAGACGGAGGAGGUGGGGUGUGGGAAGCAGGGGGCCAUGGUCUGAGCAGACCUUCUCACCUCUGGGCCUCCCACCUCCUGGGGCAGGACUUACGGGGAAGGACCCGAGGGGAGUGGGGUGUCCAUAGGGACACCCAAGGGUCUAUCCCUGCGAGCUUUGCUUUCUACUAAACCAAUAAUCGCAGUGGUGGUGGCAGUCGAGACACGGCUCAAAGAGCCGGCAAGAAUAGAGCAGAGACCAGGAUCGCCCCAGGCAGGGAAAAAAUGACCAGUUCUGUAGAGUGACCCGAAGGUGAUGGAAUCACUCGGGCGUCCUCCUGGGAAAGAGCUGCCUGCUCCCCCGCCGCCGCCAGUACACCGGCGCCCAUGCCCCGGGGGCUGGAGAGAGCAGCCAGGCACAGCCCCUCCAGCUUCCUGGGAGUCCAAUUUCCCAAGGUAGAACGGUGGCGGCAGAGCCUGGCCCUGUGGUGGGGCAGCUGCACCCCGAUGAGUGGCUUGCAGUUCCUGGAGCCCUGCAGGUUGUUGGAGAGGCAGGGAGCCCUUCUCCCUCCUGCCUGCCCUCUUGCACUUCCUCUCCCAGAACCCAGCACUACUCCCAGAGGCUCUGAGCUGGAGCCCUAGAAGGAGGCGCUGCAAGGCUCCGUGCUCCUGGAGCUUCGAGUCUAUGGUAUGAGUUAAACAGAAGGGUAUCUCCUCCAUCAGAUCUACAGGAGGGUGUCUGCUCCAUCAGACCUGGAGCUUCCAAGGCAUUUUACCCGAAGCUCCAGCACCUGGCCCAAGGCUGGGCUGUGCUGUGUCCUCAGUGAAAGAAUGGAUGAGUCACAGCUGAAUGACUGAAGAGCUGAACCAGGUCCAGAAAGACUCAGCCACUGGAGUCUGUAUUUCCUGAGUCGCCUCUCACUGGUAAGUCCUGAGCCCCGUUCCUUCCCAGCACCCACUCUUGGAGCAGCUCUCCAGGGCUGUGCUGUGGCUGCUGCGGUCAGGGAGAGGUCGCAUGCUCCAGCCAGGGUCUUUGGGGACUCAGUUUAGAACUAAUACGCCAAGCAAGUCGUGCUGAGUGUCUGGGCUUCUUCUAGGAAGGUAUUUCCAAUCAUCAAAUGUGCCAUUAAAAAAAAUGCAUGUCAGUUAAGUGUGCACUAAGCCUGGACCACAUGGGACAUAGUGGUUCCAAUAAACACGAAUAAGCCAGUUUUCACAUUAGAGAAAUACCAGUUUCUUGCAGAAAUGCGGUGCUUUUAAAAGAGGUUAAUUAAUAAACAGCAGGUAAUUGUUCGUGGCACGUUGUGGCAGAGGGUAAUUUUCAUUUUAGAGGAUGGAAGGGCCAAAUACCCCUCCCCACUCAGCAUUUUUCUGUAAUAAUCACCUCAGCUUCACCUCCGCCUUUCAUUUUUACAGCUGGAGCUGUUUAUCAUCGCUCCAACUUUCACUAAAAAGGAAAAACUAUCACUUAAACAAAGCCAUUGAAACCCCAGCAUCAUGUGUGGAUUUUUUAACAUAAAUAAAUCAUACAAACUAA